ACCUCAGGCGAUCCACUUGCCUCAGCCUCCCAAAGUGCUGGGAUUAUAGGUGUGAGCCACCGUGCCCAGCCCCCAGCUUCCACCUUUGACCCCUGGAGCCCGUUCUCUAAGGGACAGCCCAGGACUUUCAAAAACUGCAAAUCAGAUCAUUUCACUCCUCAACCAGAAUCUCCCCCUCACACUUAGAAUGAAACCAAAACCCUUCCCCAGGGCCUAAAAGUCCCAGAGAACUGGGCUCCUCCCCGACCUCAUCACAGCAGCACCACCCCUUUCUCCCCUCCUCCAAGAAGGGCAGCCGAACCACCCUCUCCCCGACAAUGAGGGCUCUUUUCAUUUCCUCCAAGAACUCACGCUUGUUCCCUCAGGAACUUUGCACUUGCUGUUCCUUAAUGCCUAGCCUUCUUUCUGGUGGCUCUUCUUGUCCUGCAGAAGUCGACUCAAACAUGACGUCCUCCUUGAAGGACCCUCCACCCCCACCCCACUCCUUACUCUCUAUCAUUUCCCGGGUCUCUUUACAGCCCUUACUGUCUCCCUGAAACUACCUGGCUCCGGCAUGUGUCCAUGCCCUCUGGACUCUAAGCUGCUUGAAGCAGUGAACUUGGUGGUCUCACGUGCCACUGACAGCAGACCCCAGAACAAGUGGAGCUCAGGAAAUGUGGGAGGAUUGAUAGCAGUGUGGGUGGAUAGACUUAGAGAUAUUGUGUCCAGGCCACAAGGCAUCAGCAGAGCCGAGCAUCAGCCAGGACAAUCUGACCUUGAACCUGACAGCUUAAUCCUGAAGCUGUGUUGCCUCUGCAGUAUUCGGUUAAGAGUUCUGCUGCCUGAGUUGGCAUCCCUGCUUUGUGAAGUUAUUGUGUGUCGGCUGGGCACGGUGUCUCAUGCCUGUAAUCCCAGCACUUUGGGAGGCCGAGGAGGGUGGAUCGCUUAAGGCCAGGAGUUCAGGACCAGCCUGGCCAACAUGGUGAAACCCCGUCUCUCCUAAGAAAACAAAAAAAUUUGCCGGGCAGGGUGGCGCACGCCAGUAAUCUUAGCUACUUGGGAGGCUGAGGCAGGAGAAUCUCUUGAACUUGGGAGGCGGACAUUGCCGUGAGCUGAGAUAGUGCCACUGCGCUCUAGCCUGGGCCAAAGAGUAAAGAUCUGUCUCAAAAUAAAUAAAUAAAUAAAAAAUAAAAACAACAAUAAAUGACUGUGUGUCCUUAGGCAAGGCACUUAGCAACUCUUGAGCUUGUUCCAUCUGUAAACCCAGGACGUUAGUGAUUCUCCCUCUAGUGGAUGAAAUGAAGCAAUGCAGAUAGAGCCCUAAUGCAGGGUACCUGCGAGUCGCUGCAGCAGCUGUGGCAAUUGUCACCUUCAUCCAGGCCCAUCCCGCUUUGAGGGCCUAGAGAGAGUGGGCCAGAGGUUAACCCCCGAUUCAUCUGCCUCCCCACGCUGGGCAUCUGGGUGUGCCAGGGCAUUCCCCCGCUGGUCAGACAGGUUUUUGGGCCAGGGCGGGGCUGACCAGGGUUAAUUAGAGGGAACUGGCUAGGAGGAGCUGGGGAGGGGGCUGGGCAGAGUCCAGGCCUCCAGAGCCCCUGGGACACAGCAGGUGUGUGCUGCCAUGGGCCGGGGCUUGAACUCUGCCAGACUCAGGCGCCAAAAACGGCGCUUGCGACCUCAGGUCCAGAAGCCCCGGCAGCAGCUGGAGCGGCUCCAGCAGGAGAACCAUGAGCUCCGGCGAGGCCUGGCAGCCCGAGGAGCCGAGUGGGAGGCCCGGGCCGUGGAGCUGGAGGGGGACGUGGAGGCCCUGCGGGCCCAGCUUGGGGAGCAGCGCUCAGAGCAGCAGGACAGUGGGCGAGAACGGGCACGGGCCCUCAGCGAGCUCAGCGAGCAGAACCUCCGGCUCAGCCAGCAGCUGGCUCAGGCCUCCCAGACUGAGCAGGAACUUCAGAGGGAACUGGACGCCCUUCGGGGACAGUGCCAGGCUCAGGCACUGGCUGGAGCAGAGCUGAGGACGCGGCUGGAGAGUCUGCAGGGGGAAAACCAGAUGCUGCAGAGCCGCCGGCAGGACCUGGAGGCCCAGAUCCGAGGCCUGCGUGAGGAGGUGGAGAAGGGUGAGGGCAGACUGCAGACCACCCACGAGGAGUUGCUGCUGCUGAGGCGGGAGCGGCGGGAGCACAGCCUGGAGCUGGAACGCGCACGGUCAGAGGCUGGGGAGGCGCUGAGUGCGCUGCGGAGGCUGCAGCGGCGCGUCUCCGAGCUGGAGGAGGAGUCACGCCUCCAGGACGCCGACGUGUCGGCUGCCUCGUUGCAGUCAGAACUGGCCCACAGCCUCGACGACGGCGACCAGGGCCAGGGCGCCGACGCACCCGGAGACACCCCGACCACCCGGUCCCCAAAGACCCGAAAGGCGUCCAGCCCCCAGCCUUCACCCCCGGAAGAGAUCUUAGAGCCCCCCAAGAAGCGAACAUCCCUCAGUCCAGCGGAGAUACUGGAGGAGAAGGAGGUGGAAGUGGCCAAGCUGCAAGAUGAGAUCUCGCUGCAGCAGGCAGAGCUGCAGUCCCUGCGGGAAGAGCUGCAGAGGCAGAAGGAGCUGCGGGCGCAGGAAGACCCUGGGGAGGCCCUGCACAGUGCCCUCUCAGACCGGGACGAGGCCGUGAACAAGGCCCUGGAGCUGUCCCUGCAGCUCAACCGCGUCUCGCUGGAGCGAGACUCCCUGUCUCGGGAGCUGCUGCGCGCCAUCCGCCAGAAGGUGGCGCUCACGCAGGAGCUGGAGGCCUGGCAGGACGACAUGCAGGUGGUGAUCGGGCAGCAGCUGCGCUCACAGCGCCAGAAGGAGCUGAGCGCCUCCGCGUCGUCGUCGACCCCGCGCCGUGCCGCGCCCCGCUUCUCGCUGCGCCUGGGCCCCGGGCCCGCCGGUGGCUUUCUCAGUAACCUCUUCCGAAGGACCUGACGGCUGGGCCCAGAGGGCUGCCCUUGCCCACUUAGGGGCUCACUUUCCUCUUCAGGCCAAUGGAGCGACAGGGCCCAGAUUGUCUUCCAAAAGAAGCUGAUGCCCUCCCCGCCCCAGGAUGCUGGGCAAGGGCUCAUCGGGAGCAGGGGCUCAUCCGGAGCAGGGGCCAGCUUUGUGGGGCAGGAGCUCCAGGUGGGUGGCAGGGGCAGGUGAACAGAGCUAUUUUCCGAAUUAAUAUACGUCUAUCUUUUCUAGGGCAGGGAUGGGGCUGGGUAUUUAUGUAUCAAGAUCGGACAGAGUAAUAUAUAAAUCACUCCACCGAUUUGGCCCCCAUUCAUAGAAAGAAAGAGCAUGGUAAAAAAGCCUGAAACUUUAUUGUAAAAAAAAAAAAAAAAAGAAAAUGAAAAACACUCUAAAACCCUGA